AACAGCCUCCAGUGAAUCUGAUCCAUGUGUAAGGAAAACAGGAUGCGUCCCUGGACCGGCUGGUAGCAAGAUUUAUGUUUCAGAAUAUUGCAACAUAACUUCCUUCCCUCUGUUGCCUUUGUGCAUUGUUUGAAGGAGGAGAAUAAAGGACUACUUUUGCAGCACAGCAGUCUGUAAAGAUGGAUGGCAUGGGGUUAGUUUAAAUAGCAUAUUGGCCUUUCUGGGUCACUGUGGGCAACCUUGUCCCUGGUUUAUUUUAACACCUGCUUUAAUGCCUCCAUGAUACAACUGAAUGGGCAUCUUUCAUUCAUUCGUCUGUUACUUCUGAAUGAAGCUACUUGGGGUUCGUUAGAAUGAUGGCAAGUGAGAAUGCAGUCGUCUCUAGGUCAUUACUUGUAAUACGUUCUGAGGACUGCCUUUGCUGAUGGGGGGAGAAGGACUCUCACAGCUGUAGCCAGCGUUCAUGUUUGGUCAUUGCUGGAACUCUCAGGAAGCCUGAAACUGUGAACUUUGUAGCAGAAAAGGGUGAGUGGUGGUUUUGUAUUUGUGUGUAAAUUAUCCUGCUAUAUGCAAUCAAGGAAAUGAAUGUGGACGCUUUCAAGGCUACUUGGUUAUUCUAGUGGGAAUAUAGAUACUUUACUUUUCUUCAUUUGGCUUUCAGUUAUAUUCUAAAUUUUGCAAAAAUGGACAUAUAUUAUGUACCUAUCAAAAAGUUAAAAAUAACAAAUAUUGGCAGUUCAACAGACCAUGAGCAUUUGAGGAGUAGGGAAUCUGCCUGUCUUGUUCACUGACAUUUUUCUAGAUAUUUUCUCAGAAAAUAGCAGAAAGUAAGAACUCAACAAAUACUUGUUGCAUAAUGAGUGAGUUGAUCUUCAUGUGUUUAUUGAUAGAAUGAACUGCGUUAGGUAAUGUGAAGAUUAUAUACAAAGCACAAAAGAAGGCCUGUGUCCUAAAGGACUUUAAAUCUAGUUUGGGAGGCAAAAUGAACAAAUGUAAAACAAUUAGGAAACCAUGCAAGGCUGUGUAUACAAAUAUACAAGUAUAUGCAUAUGUUUUUAGUUCUUAGCAAUUCGAAAACAAUACAAGACUGUAUAUUCAUGUAUAUGUAUAUAUGUGUAUGUACCUACAUAGGAUUAUAUAUAUAUUUGCAAUUUGCAAACAUUGCGAGCUCGUGUAUGCAUAUAUGCAUGCAUAUAUAUGUGUGUGUAUGUAUGUGUAUUUCUAGCUGAGGAGAUAAACAGCAAGAAUAAAUUCACAAAGCCUUGUAAGAGAAGAGCAGAGCGUUUUCAUAGACGGGAUGUGGAGGUCCUGGAAGCACAGCCCAGCAGAUGACUCACCUCUGGAUGGAAUCAACACACAAAGCAGAUAAAAAGCUGAACAUUAAAGACCACAUUGUUAAAGCAGAGAGCCAAAUUGUUCCUCCACCAUUCCCUAUCCCAGACUUCACAUCUAACAAGAAGAUAGAUGAAGAGAAUGAGGCAAACUUGCUAGCAGUCCUCACAGAGACACUAGACAGUCUCCCUGUGGAUGAAGACGGAUUGCCCUCAUUUGAUGCGCUGACAGAUGGAGACGUGACCACUGACAAUGAGGCUAGUCCUUCCUCCAUGCCUGACGGCACCCCUCCACCCCAGGAGGCAGAAGAGCCGUCUCUACUUAAGAAGCUCUUACUGGCACCAGCCAACACUCAGCUAAGUUAUAAUGAAUGCAGUGGUCUCAGUACCCAGAACCAUGCAAAUCACAAUCACAGGAUCAGAACAAACCCUGCAAUUGUUAAGACUGAGAAUUCAUGGAGCAAUAAAGCGAAGAGUAUUUGUCAACAGCAAAAGCCACAAAGACGUCCCUGCUCGGAGCUUCUCAAAUAUCUGACCACAAACGAUGACCCUCCUCACACCAAACCCACAGAGAACAGAAACAGCAGCAGAGACAAAUGCACCUCCAAAAAGAAGUCCCACACACAGUCGCAGUCACAACACUUACAAGCCAAACCAACAACUUUAUCUCUUCCUCUGACCCCAGAGUCACCAAAUGACCCCAAGGGUUCCCCAUUUGAGAACAAGACUAUUGAACGCACCUUAAGUGUGGAACUCUCUGGAACUGCAGGCCUAACUCCACCCACCACUCCUCCUCAUAAAGCCAACCAAGAUAACCCUUUUAGGGCUUCUCCAAAGCUGAAGUCCUCUUGCAAGACUGUGGUGCCACCACCAUCAAAGAAGCCCAGGUACAGUGAGUCUUCUGGUACACAAGGCAAUAACUCCACCAAGAAAGGGCCGGAGCAAUCCGAGUUGUAUGCACAACUCAGCAAGUCCUCAGUCCUCACUGGUGGACACGAGGAAAGGAAGACCAAGCGGCCCAGUCUGCGGCUGUUUGGUGACCAUGACUAUUGCCAGUCAAUUAAUUCCAAAACAGAAAUACUCAUUAAUAUAUCACAGGAGCUCCAAGACUCUAGACAACUAGAAAAUAAAGAUGUCUCCUCUGAUUGGCAGGGGCAGAUUUGUUCUUCCACAGAUUCAGACCAGUGCUACCUGAGAGAGACUUUGGAGGCAAGCAAGCAGGUCUCUCCUUGCAGCACAAGAAAACAGCUCCAAGACCAGGAAAUCCGAGCCGAGCUGAACAAGCACUUCGGUCAUCCCAGUCAAGCUGUUUUUGACGACGAAGCAGACAAGACCGGUGAACUGAGGGACAGUGAUUUCAGUAAUGAACAAUUCUCCAAACUACCUAUGUUUAUAAAUUCAGGACUAGCCAUGGAUGGCCUGUUUGAUGACAGCGAAGAUGAAAGUGAUAAACUGAGCUACCCUUGGGAUGGCACGCAAUCCUAUUCAUUGUUCAAUGUGUCUCCUUCUUGUUCUUCUUUUAACUCUCCAUGUAGAGAUUCUGUGUCACCACCCAAAUCCUUAUUUUCUCAAAGACCCCAAAGGAUGCGCUCUCGUUCAAGGUCCUUUUCUCGACACAGGUCGUGUUCCCGAUCACCAUAUUCCAGGUCAAGAUCAAGGUCUCCAGGCAGUAGAUCCUCUUCAAGAUCCUGCUAUUACUAUGAGUCAAGCCACUACAGACACCGCACGCACCGAAAUUCUCCCUUGUAUGUGAGAUCACGUUCAAGAUCGCCCUACAGCCGUCGGCCCAGGUAUGACAGCUACGAGGAAUAUCAGCACGAGAGGCUGAAGAGGGAAGAAUAUCGCAGAGAGUAUGAGAAGCGAGAGUCUGAGAGGGCCAAGCAAAGGGAGAGGCAGAGGCAGAAGGCAAUUGAAGAGCGCCGUGUGAUUUAUGUCGGUAAAAUCAGACCUGACACAACACGGACAGAACUGAGGGACCGUUUUGAAGUUUUUGGUGAAAUUGAGGAGUGCACAGUAAAUCUGCGGGAUGAUGGAGACAGCUAUGGUUUCAUUACCUACCGUUAUACCUGUGAUGCUUUUGCUGCUCUUGAAAAUGGAUACACUUUGCGCAGGUCAAACGAAACUGACUUUGAGCUGUACUUUUGUGGACGCAAGCAAUUUUUCAAGUCUAACUAUGCAGACCUAGAUUCAAACUCAGAUGACUUUGACCCUGCUUCCACCAAGAGCAAGUAUGACUCUCUGGAUUUUGAUAGUUUACUGAAAGAAGCUCAGAGAAGCUUGCGCAGGUAACAUGUUCCCUAGCUGAGGAUGACAGAGGGAUGGCGAAUACCUCAUGGGACAGCGCGUCCUUCCCUAAAGACUAUUGCAAGUCAUACUUAGGAAUUUCUCCUACUUUACACUCUCUGUACAAAAACAAAACAAAACAACAACAAUACAACAAGAACAACAACAACAAUAACAACAAUGGUUUACAUGAACACAGCUGCUGAAGAGGCAAGAGACAGAAUGAUAUCCAGUAAGCACAUGUUUAUUCAUGGGUGUCAGCUUUGCUUUUCCUGGAGUCUCUUGGUGAUGGAGUGUGCGUGUGUGCAUGUAUGUGUGUGUGUAUGUAUGUGUGUGGUGUGUGUGCUUGGUUUAGGGGAAGUAUGUGUGGGUACAUGUGAGGACUGGGGGCACCUGACCAGAAUGCGCAAGGGCAAACCAUUUCAAAUGGCAGCAGUUCCAUGAAGACACGCUUAAAACCUAGAACUUCAAAAUGUUCGUAUUCUAUUCAAAAGGAAAUAUAUAUAUAUAUAUAUAUAUAUAUAUAUAUAUAUAUAAAUUAAAAAGGAAAGAAAACUAACAACCAACCAACCAACCAACCAACCACAAACCACCCUAAAAUGACAGCCGCUGAUGUCUGGGCAUCAGCCUUUGUACUCUGUUUUUUUAAGAAAGUGCAGAAUCAACUUGAAGCAAGCUUUCUCUCAUAACGUAAUGAUUAUAUGACAAUCCUGAAGAAACCACAGGUUCCAUAGAACUAAUAUCCUGUCUCUCUCUCUCUCUCUCUCUCUCUCUUUUUUUUUUCUUUUUCCUUUUGCCAUGGAAUCUGGGUGGGAGAGGAUACUGCGGGCACCAGAAUGCUAAAGUUUCCUAACAUUUUGAAGUUUCUGUAGUUCAUCCUUAAUCCUGACACCCAUGUAAAUGUCCAAAAUGUUGAUCUUCCACUGCAAAUUUCAAAAGCCUUGUCAAUGGUCAAGCGUGCAGCUUGUUCAGCGGUUCUUUCUGAGGAGCGGACACCGGGUUACAUUACUAAUGAGAGUUGGGUAGAACUCUCUGAGAUGUGUUCAGAUAGUGUAAUUGCUACAUUCUCUGAUGUAGUUAAGUAUUUACAGAUGUUAAAUGGAGUAUUUUUAUUUUAUGUAUAUACUAUACAACAAUGUUCUUUUUUGUUACAGCUAUGCACUGUAAAUGCAGCCUUCUUUUCAAAACUGCUAAAUUUUUCUUAAUCAAGAAUAUUCAAAUGUAAUUAUGAGGUGAAACAAUUAUUGUACACUAACAUAUUUAGAAGCUGAACUUACUGCUUAUAUAUAUUUGAUUGUAAAAACAAAAAGACAGUGUGUGUGUCUGUUGAGUGCAACAAGAGCAAAAUGAUGCUUUCCGCACAUCCAUCCCUUAGGUGAGCUUCAAUCUAAGCAUCUUGUCAAGAAAUAUCCUAGUCCCCUAAAGGUAUUAACCACUUCUGCGAUAUUUUUCCACAUUUUCUUGUCGCUUGUUUUUCUUUGAAGUUUUAUACACUGGAUUUGUUAGGGGAAUGAAAUUUUCUCAUCUAAAAUUUUUCUAGAAGAUAUCAUGAUUUUAUGUAAAGUCUCUCAAUGGGUAACCAUUAAGAAAUGUUUUUAUUUUCUCUAUCAACAGUAGUUUUGAAACUAGAAGUCAAAAAUCUUUUUAAAAUGCUGUUUUGUUUUAAUUUUUGUGAUUUUAAUUUGAUACAAAAUGCUGAGGUAAUAAUUAUAGUAUGAUUUUUACAAUAAUUAAUGUGUGUCUGAAGACUAUCUUUGAAGCCAGUAUUUCUUUCCCUUGGCAGAGUAUGACGAUGGUAUUUAUCUGUAUUUUUUACAGUUAUGCAUCCUGUAUAAAUACUGAUAUUUCAUUCCUUUGUUUACUAAAGAGACAUAUUUAUCAGUUGCAGAUAGCCUAUUUAUUAUAAAUUAUGAGAUGAUGAAAAUAAUAAAGCCAGUGGAAAUUUUCUACCUAGGAUGCAUGACAAUUGUCAGGUUGGAGUGUAAGUGCUUCAUUUGGGAAAUUCAGCUUUUGCAGAAGCAGUGUUUCUACUUGCACUAGCAUGGCCUCUGACGUGACCAUGGUGUUGUUCUUGAUGACAUUGCUUCUGCUAAAUUUAAUAAAAACUUCAGAAAAACCUCCAUUUUGAUCAUCAGGAUUUCAUCUGAGUGUGGAGUCCCUGGAAUGGAAUUCAGUAACAUUUGGAGUGUGUAUUCAAGUUUCUAAAUUGAGAUUCGAUUACUGUUUGGCUGACAUGACUUUUCUGGAAGACAUGAUACACCUACUACUCAAUUGUUCUUUUCCUUUCUCUCGCCCAACACGAUCUUGUAAGAUGGAUUUCACCCCCAGGCCAAUGCAGCUAAUUUUGAUAGCUGCAUUCAUUUAUCACCAGCAUAUUGUGUUCUGAGUGAAUCCACUGUUUGUCCUGUCGGAUGCUUGCUUGAUUUUUUGGCUUCUUAUUUCUAAGUAGAUAGAAAGCAAUAAAAAUACUAUGAAAUGAAAGAACUUGUUCACAGGUUCUGCGUUACAACAGUAACACAUCUUUAAUCCGCCUAAUUCUUGUUGUUCUGUAGGUUAAAUGCAGGUAUUUUAACUGUGUGAACGCCAAACUAAAGUUUACAGUCUUUCUUUCUGAAUUUUGAGUAUCUUCUGUUGUAGAAUAAUAAUAAAAAGACUAUUAAGAGCAAUAAAUUAUUUUUAAGAAAUCGAGAUUUAGUAAAUCCUAUUAUGUGUUCAAGGACCACAUGUGUUCUCUAUUUUGCCUUUAAAUUUUUGUGAACCAAUUUUAAAUACAUUCUCCUUUUUGCCCUGGAUUGUUGACAUGAGUGGAAUACUUGGUUUCUUUUCUUACUUAUCAAAAGACAGCACUACAGAUAUCAUAUUGAGGAUUAAUUUAUCCCCCCUACCCCCAGCCUGACAAAUAUUGUUACCAUGAAGAUAGUUUUCCUCAAUGGACUUCAAAUUGCAUCUAGAAUUAGUGGAGCUUUUGUAUCUUCUGCAGACACUGUGGGUAGCCCAUCAAAAUGUAAGCUGUGCUCCUCUCAUUUUUAUUUUUAUUUUUUUGGGAGAGAAUAUUUCAAAUGAACACGUGCACCCCAUCAUCACUGGAGGCAAAUUUCAGCAUAGAUCUGUAGGAUUUUUAGAAGACCGUGGGCCAUUGCCUUCAUGCCGUGGUAAGUACCACAUCUACAAUUUUGGUAACCGAACUGGUGCUUUAGUAAUGUGGAUUUUUUUCUUUUUUAAAAGAGAUGUAGCAGAAUAAUUCUUCCAGUGCAACAAAAUCAAUUUUUUGCUAAACGACUCCGAGAACAACAGUUGGGCUGUCAACAUUCAAAGCAGCAGAGAGGGAACUUUGCACUAUUGGGGUAUGAUGUUUGGGUCAGUUGAUAAAAGGAAACCUUUUCAUGCCUUUAGAUGUGAGCUUCCAGUAGGUAAUGAUUAUGUGUCCUUUCUUGAUGGCUGUAAUGAGAACUUCAAUCACUGUAGUCUAAGACCUGAUCUAUAGAUGACCUAGAAUAGCCAUGUACUAUAAUGUGAUGAUUCUAAAUUUGUACCUAUGUGACAGACAUUUUCAAUAAUGUGAACUGCUGAUUUGAUGGAGCUACUUUAAGAUUUGUAGGUGAAAGUGUAAUACUGUUGGUUGAACUAUGCUGAAGAGGGAAAGUGAGCGAUUAGUUGAGCCCUUGCCGGGCCUUUUUUCCACCUGCCAAUUCUACAUGUAUUGUUGUGGUUUUAUUCAUUGUAUGAAAAUUCCUGUGAUUUUUUUUAAAUGUGCAGUACACAUCAGCCUCACUGAGCUAAUAAAGGGAAACGAAUGUUUCAAAUCUA